ACGGCGGGUAUAGAGGAGGAAGGCUGGGGCUGGGUUGCCGGCUGCUGGCGGCUGGAGGUCCGCGCCCAGUGUAGGGAAGUCUUCGAAGGAGGCUGCCAGGCUGGAGGCUGGGACCAGCUCCUGGGGGCGGGGGCCCUUCUUCGUCUGCCUGCGUGCGCGGAGCCGCUGUGACAGCUGGGCGCCUUCGCCUUGUUCACGUUGGUUAAGUUAAUUGUACCGAGUUCUCGGGAAUGAAGUGUGGCUCCGGGAUGCCCCGCAGAGGGAUGUGACAAGCCGGUCAGUGAGGCUGAGCAAAGGGGCUAACCUUGCCUCUGGGCGCCCUAGCAGUGCCCCCAGCCCCUCUUUAUCAGCUGCAAUUCCUGAGUGUUGUGGGAUGCCUCGGUGGGUUAGGGUAGCCACCCAGCGUUGGGGCAGAAAGGCCUCGGAGGGCAUCUGCACCCCCGAGGGGCCCUGAAGUAAACUGAGGCCUAGAGAUUUGCCCAGCGUUUCUCCUGGACCCUCCUUGGACCUUCCUGGACCAUUAUCCAUCCCCCGCUUUCCUGCUUCUCCUCCCAGGACCGGCAACCUUGCAAAAUCAGGAACCCUCCCUUCCAGAACAUGGCACUUACUAAUUUUACAAACUGAAUGUUGAACUAGGAUCUCUUGAUUGAUACAUAAAGACAUACAUAGAUCAUAUAUGAUUUUAUUCAAAGUAGUAUAGGAAUAAAAAUGCCUUCUAAGUAGGUAGGUUUUUGCAAACAAGUUUUUCUCCCCCAAGUUCCUGAGAAACUGUCAGAAGAUUUUCUUUCUUGCCACCUCCUAGAUGGGCACACAGAGCUGGUGAGGUAAAGUGGCUUGUUAUGGCCUUCCUGUGGGCACAUAGGUGAGCUGGAGGUGGAGCUGCAGGUCUGGGCUUCCCUCCAAAGUCCAGCUCCGGAGGAGAGCCAGCUCAGGAGCCCUCUGCAGAAGUCCAACCCUGUCUUUGCGGCUCUCUCCUCUGGGCUUUGGAUGAUUGCAGUGAGCUGGCUUGUAGGUGAAGCAUGCAGGGGUAAUUCAUCCAGGAUAUUGUCCAGGGGGGUGGCAGGCAGGUCGGCCCACAGUGGUCACAUGUGUGCCUUGCUUUUCUUGGAUGAUCAAAGCUCGCCAUGUCUGAGCCACUGUCCUGGCCAGGGACCCAGCACGGUCACCGUGGCUGCUGUGAGGGCUGCAGUUUCCUUCCACACCUUUGUCAUCCCUGGUUGCUGCUGCCCCUGGCCAGGAAAAGUGAGAUAUCAGAAACAUUUGAUUUUUCACAUGCCUGGAAGAGAGAAGAUUAAUUCCUGCAUCAAGAAGAAGUGUUUGGGGAAAGGUUGGUAACGUGGGAAGCGGAUUCUACUUAUUUGGCGUCUUGAGAAACAGCAGACAAGAAAUUCCAAGUUAACUAGCUGGGCCCCAGGAGUCUGCAGUAGGGGAAGCUGUAGAUUAGUGCUGGACUGUGGUAGUCCAAGCCAUUUCGAGUUCGGCUGGAAGGUCCCCUGCUAGUGGAGGGGGCUGGGGAGAAGAGGGAGACCCCAGGGCUGUCCUGAACAGGUGAGCACAUGCCCAUCUACAGGGGACAGACUAGACUCAGCUCCAGCCAGUUGGGGGGAAAACAGUGUCAACAGGUCUUGUGAAUUUUCGAGAGGAUUCUCCAGCCUGGGUAUUUAAAUGUGGGCUCAAAUUCUAGAAGUAUGGUAGAGGGUUAGGGGUGAGUGCCCUUCCAGGAGGUCUGAAGCUUGCCAUCUGGCCCGGUGCUUAUCUAUUGGGAAGGGUGUCACUGCAUCAGAGAGCAGGGCACAGGAGCCACACCCAUUGUGGGCCCAGGGACUAAGAACUGAUGGCUGCCCAUCAUGCCUGCGGCCAGGUCCCUAGGCUGGAGGUGAGGCGGGCAGAGCUCCUUCAUGUACUCGUGUGCCAUGUGUUCAUUCAGCAGCUGUUGAAUGAAUUGCCAUGAUGUAGAAAGUCAUCUGCAUGAACCUUUUCAUAUAAUUCCUUUCACCAAAUAGAUCCUACAGCUGAGCCUCUGGGAUGAUUUGGCGGGGCUAGGACAGACAGGGUCCCAGCCCUCAUGGGAUGGGGACAAGCGGAAUUGGCUGUGUAGACAGACAAAUGGUCCAGAAGCUGCCAUAAGAGCCCAGAAGGGUGGUGAUGCAAAGCAAGGCUUGGGAGCAGGGGUCAGGGAGUGGAGGGUGGACUCGGGGGAGUGUGAGGAGUCUCCUUUUCAGGUGUGGACAUUGAAUUUCAGAGCAGUGGGUGGGAGGCACCCACCCCCUGAACAGGGGAUGCUCAGGUAUGAUAUUAAGUUGGGAGUGACUUGCCCAAGGUCACAUAGCCAGUAAGUGGAAAGUCAGGGGGUCUCUGAUCUCCAGCUCUUGGCCAGCUCCUUCAUCUCCACUGUACUGGGCUGAGGCCUCUUAGAAACUCCCAGAGGUGUGGACACUCCCUGUAAUUGGCAGCUGUCAUUUUUCCCAUCUACACGUUCAGGCCCUGUCCCCGUUCCUAGGGCCUCAGCAGGCCCAGGAUUGCAGAGAUGCCAUUUGGAGCAUAUUUGUAUGAAAGAAGAGUCGUCUAAAUUCUAAAAGCAGAGACUGUUUUUAAAAGUGGUAGCUGACUUGGGAGUGUCAUUGAUCUGAGCAAUCAGCCAGCGGACUUCUCUUUAGCAGCUUGUGAUUUGGAAGUGACUCAGUCACUGGUGAGAAUCACGCAGCCUCCCUCCCCUUCUGGUCUGUAAAGGGGAUGCUCAGGUAUGAGAUUAAGUUACUUCAAAGGGUCACUCUGUUCCAGUGCUGUGAAUGAGGAGAUCAUGUUUGCACUUAGCUGGCUAAGUGUUGGGAGGCUGAGUGUUUCCACUGCUCAAGGCAUUUCUUCAUUGGCCUGCAGUAUGAGGGUCUGAUUUCUUUACUGAGAUAGUUUCUCCUUUCAAAUAAAGCACUGGGACAAAAUGAUUUAUGUGUAGACCUGUGUCUCCACAGCAGGAGAUGGACCAUAAAUGGAACAGUUAUCUAAUUAGUGUGUCCAGUCUAGGUGUCUAGUUAGGAGUGUCCAGGAAGAAGGAGAAAGGUUUUGUGUCCAUUUGGGCCAACAUAGAUUUUUUAAAUUGUAACUAUGGGAGUUGGGGAGGAAGACAGUUCAUCGCAAGACCUAUCACGUGCUGCGUCCCUAUAGGUUUGAAGCUGGCCCUCUGCUAGACAGGUCACACAGGUAUAUCCCUUUGUGUCCUUUAAAGGGCUGGGAAGCUGUUGGAGAUGACACACACCAAGCUCUCAGCCAUCCGGAUGUGCAGGAGGAGGGAUUGGGAAUGACGGUAGAGGCAGGAGGGAAAUAAGGGGGUGAGGGGAGAAGAACAACUGUGGCUCCAGAAGGAGGAGGCGGCGUGAAUCAGCAAGUGGUUAAGUUGUGGGGAGGUGGCAAGUGGGAAGCAGUUUCUCAUCUUCGCUGAUUUCCAAAGGGAUGGAGAGGAAAGGAGGCUGUCUGCAGCAGGACCUGCAGCGUUUCUGCCCUGCAACCCUGGGCCAGGUGCAUGGGGGCAGAGAGCCAGCGCUCAGCACAGAGCACAGCACUCAGAUCAGUGGGCGAGGCGGAGCUCGUGCAAGUCAGAGUUAUGUAACGCCGUUGACAGGCACCUUAUGGGGCUUGGCAAAGUGCAGCAGGAGCCCGGGGUAGCGACUUUGAGAUUGGAGUGUUCCGGGAAGACUUCGCCCCCUGGCUUGAGGGCGGGUGUCUUUUCAGAGUUAAUACCUGCCAGUGCUUGGCACAGUGCCUGGCAUCCAGUAAGUGCUCAGUAAACACUGGCUCGGGUGAUAUUCUUCAGCCCCGGAGCUCCUAACCGUGCAUGUCUCCAUAUUUGAUUCCAGUAUAUUCUACCUCAAAGGAUAUAGGCAGGAGCCCCUGCAAGCCUUGGCUCCAGCUAGGUUUCCUUAGGGUGGUGGCUUCACUCUCUGGACUCUGUCUCCUCAUCUGUGCGAGGAGAACACUGGUAAACAGCUACCCUUCAAGACCCUUCAGCUGACCUUGCAGCCAGGCUGUGGAGCAGCUCCGCUGUGCCCAUAUUUGAUGCAAUUAACCAGAGAGAGGAGACCGCGUGGCUCUAGGUGGAACUGUGCUGGUGUAGCUCGCUUGUGAAUGUUACAUCUCACCCCACUCUCAGCUUAAAAGAGCCCAGAGGGGGCCUGGAGGGCGGGGGGGUGGGGGCUCCUGGCUUCGGCAGGCUCUCCCUGAUGCCUAUUUUACAUUUCUAGAACUUAUCGUGGCCCAGGCCUCUUAGAUCUCUGAAGAAAGUAAGGCUGGCAGAUCCUCAAAAGCAGAGGGUAUCAUUAUAAUGGAAACUUGGACACUUUCCAGAAUUGCAUUUGUGGUAAAAAUAUUGAAACAGACAGUCCAGGCACCCAGGUGCCUGGAAAAUACCCCAACAUGGGCAAAUAAUUAGAUACAGGCCAGGCACAAUUAUGUUUUUCUGACAAUAGGCUGGAACUCGGUGGCUUAGCAUUUUCUCUUGAAACAGAAUACGCCCCUGCCGGACCCUUUUGCUCCCUGUGGUCAAAAAGAUAGUGGUGUGGCCAGCAAGGGGGAGGGCAUACAAGGAGAAGUGGCGAUCCCAUCCCUCCCAGGGUGGCCCUGGAUCUAUCUCAGGGAGGUUCUGUCCUGCUUUUGCUUUUCUGUGUCCCUGUAGGUAGCUGUCCCGAGGGACUGGGCCCGUGGCACCUUUGCUAGGAGGCCAGAGCCUGCAUUUCAGAGUCUAAGAGGUCGAGAGAGGUGUAAGAUGUAUUAUCUUACCCUUCCACGAAAGUGGUCUGGGCAGCUGUGUUCCCUUUUGUAACCCCUGGCAGCUCACUCAUGCUGAUGGCGGUAAGUUCACCUGUACCUUCACGUUUCUUGUCAGCCAAAUAUUUGGCGCCCGUGACACGGAAGCUCUUUUAGCCCAGGUGUUAGAUCGCAUAGGCACUGGGUGGGGCAGGGCAGGUAGUGGGUUGAGCCUGGGAUCCACGCUGACUCAGGUUCAAGUUCAUGCAGUGCUGCUUCGUCCCAUUACUGUGGCUCUGAACAAGUGGCUUAGCUUGCAUCUCGGUUUCCCCAUCUGUAAAAUGGGGUUAAUGAUCUCUACCUGGUUGGGUGGCUUGAGUAUUUGAAAUAGUACAAUUCAGGGUUCAGGGGAGCUCCCCACAUGGAAUCACUUUUUUCUGGGUGAGGUCUAAACCUAUGGAGAGAUAGAGGAGGAGGAGGAGGAGGAGGAGGAGGAGGAAGGCAGGUGGAAAUCCACAUGCGAUGGCUGUUCCCGACUGCAGCUGUUGUUGGAGAAUGUGGCUGAACCAGUGGGCAAGGAAGUGGGGAACAGGGGCAGUCAGGCAGACCCGCCCACCCCAUUGCCUGCGGAGCUGGAGGAGCCUCUCCCAGCAGGGCGAAGGGCCUCCUUACCAUGGGGAAAGGCAGGGCUGGGCUGUCAUGUCCACGCCCUCCUUCCAUAUUCCUGGGAUGGUGUAGAAACCACCACGUAUAGACAACAGGAAAGUUACACAGGGGAGCUUCCUCCUCAUGGAAGGAAACAUCUGGGGUGGCGGAGAACAGUCGCCCUGUGGCAAGGAAUAUGAUGUGCUGGGCUCCGUGCCCGGCCCACGGUUGGAGGGUGGUCAAUGGCAUCUGUUAGGUACGUACUUGGUAGAAGUGGCCACAGUGUGUCAAAUCGGUGUUGUUGUCUGCUGUAGGAAAUAAUCUGGCUUUAAAUUCAAGAACAUCUCUUUCCUACUUGUUGGCAGAGCAUGAUUGAGGUAAUGGUGAUCCAUGGAUCUCAAGGUCACAUUCUAAGUUGAACGCAAUUCACAGGGAGCUGAGGUAGUGGUUGACUCCUAGCCUGGGCCUGGAGAAGCUUCUCUGCCUCCUCUCUCUUGGUCCCAGCCCCCCACAGGGCCUGUGCUUUUACCAGACCUGGUUCUGUGUUUGCAACGAGACGCCUGGCCAGCCGGGCCUGGACCUGGCUACACUUGGGUCCCCCGGCCACUGGAGAGGGGGAGCCCCCACAUUUGCCUACUUCAUCAUCGAGCCCCCCACCCCCACUGCCUUCAGGAAGCGUUUGCCAGUCAUUCUUGCUAUCUGCUCCCCGUACCUCCCUUCCCCAGCCAGGUGUGGAUCCUUCCUCCUCUGAGCUUCUGCAGUUUUCCUCUGUUGUAUUUCUCAACCUUGACCCUGUCCCACACUGUGCUGGGCUCCAGUUUCCUGGGUGCAGUCUGCUCUCCCAGCCUGAUGAGGCUCUCUUCAGGAGGAGGGUGUCUGGGGCUCACGGUACAUCCAUGUAGCUGGACUCUCACUUAGUGGCCAGUGACUGCCAUGUGCUGCAUUAACGCGUCAAUUAAAAAUGAUUCUUCCAAAGGCUAGGUUCUCCUGGAGGUUUUAUGUGAACACUGAGUUUGAUAGUGUGGCACAGGAGAGCUCACACUUGUCACUCAAUUUCCCAAGGAGUCGAGAGUCUAAUGGAAUAACCUUGGAUUUCCUGGCAUUAGGUUUUGGGGCUAUUAAAACAUAGUGACCACAGUUUUUUGUGUCUUGAGAGCCUUAGGGGAAAAUGUUAUGGAAAUUUGGUUGUUGUUUCAGGAAUAUAAGCGGAGCCGUCUACUCAGGCGAGAAAUGUGGAGGCUGCUGGUGUUUCUUAUAGCUGGUAUAAAUAGCUUGGCUUCAAGUUCCAUGCUCCUUUGUUUGGAAUGUAAAUAUUUGCAUUAAAAAUAUAAAGUAUGUCCUGGCAUGUAUUUUUAGGGACUAUAAUUUCCAAACCCCAAAUCAGACUAUGGGUCUACUGAGGAUUAAUUUUCUCUGCUUUGUGAACCUGUGUAUGUAAAGAGUCUUCCAAAUGUACACACCAAACCCUGUUUGCUUUGUGCAUGGAAGGAACCGCCAGGAUUACAAGAAAGCAGGGUUGCCCCGGGGAGUGUGGGCCGAGGGCUUGUGUUUCUCUCCACACACUUCUGAUGGUUCUGCCUGGUAGCUGCAGCGGCUCAGGGCGGUGGGGUGGAGGAGUUUUGGCCGAGAUCUUGUGGGUAUCAUCAGGGGCCUGGCUUCUCUGUUGUUGGUUUCCUGGACAUCCAGGUGGGGAUUUGGCUGCAGCUGGCUGACCUCUGUGUCACGUAACCAGACGCUUGACUUUGGAGUUGCAGUUGCUCUAGGAAGAUGUUCGGGAGUUUUAGUGCCCUUUCUGUGGUCUGGUGGAGGGAGCAGGAGGUUCUCAUGUCCGGUUCAGAGGUGAACUGUGAAGGCCUCUGUGUGGUGUCUUCCUCCACUGGAUUCCUGGGGGCUGUUUAGCUUUAAUUUUUCUAUGAAGGACAACCUGGAUGAUUGGUUAAUCCCUUACUGUGGGUGGGAUGUCAUCUCUGGUCUGGCCUCGGCCUGUUCUCGGUAGUGGGGGGCUUGAUGGGCAGCAGGAGCUGGGCAGGCCAUUUGCCCCUGGUAUGGGGGAGCUUGUUCCUAAGGCUCUCUGGGCAGCCUUCAAUGGUCACCUUCUGGCCCAAAGGCUCUAACGGAGAAGGUUGGGCCAUGGAGGUCAGCUGGCCUGCAGGGGAGGACCGAAUGCAGGUGGGCCCCCAACUGGCAACCUCCCUCUUGUCUCAUCACAGGAUGAAGGGCAGAUGAGAAGACAGCCAGGAGGGUCCUGGGCCCUCAGCUGUGACUCCCCGAGAGGCAGGUACCAAGGGCUUCCUUUGUCCUUGCUUCCCAGCCAGCGCGUGGCCCCUGCCCUUGGGAGGGUCAGCUCCUCCUCCGUCCCACUGAACACUGAUGCCUCAGGACUGGACUCCUUGGGGCAGCAGAGACCCUUCCGUCUUUCCUUCCCUAGCUCUGCCUUGCAAAGGUGCAGCCUCCUGAGCCUCAGAGUGUCUGACAUCUCUCUGCCUAGGCACCCUCUCUGAAACAUUGUGUGGGCUUAGAAACCGUGAGCCUUGGGAAGGACCAUCUUCCUCUGAGCUCUGGGCGUGUUGAACUGCGGAGGCUUACCACUUCCUCGCCUGUGGUCAUCUCCAGCCUGACCCAUGGUGGCGUGAUCCUCUCUCAUCAUCCGUCACAGUUUUUAAUAAAGAAAAUAUGUUCCAGAAAGGCCGAGUCCCCAUGCCGCAUCAGGUCAGUGAUCCAAGUGCAUUAUAGUGAAAGUCAGAGGAAAUAGCUGCUUUUAGGACACGCUGAACUUGCCUAAGAAAGUUAUUAGUGGGAAUAAAUGAGGGGGAAGAAAGCAUGCUCCGACUAACGAGAACAGUAUCAGCCUGACAUUUUGUGUCGUCCUAACUUUGAAAAGCUAUUUAUACCCACUUGCUAGCAGUUUCUAUGAGAAAUUAGAUAUGAGGAGAUGUACAGAAGAGAAGAGUGGGAGCUGGGUGACUGUGAGCUCCUCCUCAGAAACAUCUUCCAGGCAAAAAAAAGGAAAAGAAAAAAUCAUUUGCUCACCUAUCGACAAUAGAAAAUCCAGGGAUCUUUUGCAUUGUAUAAAAUUUGGCUCAGAGAAGAAAAAUGAUGUAUUGAAAAGAAGAUGAAGCUUCAGUUGCCAUUUGAGUGGUGGAAAAUAAAUUUGCUUUCGGCCCUUAAAAUGGAAAUAAGUCGAUAGAAAAAUGCAGGCCUGCCCCCUUUUGAGUCAGCAGUUUUUUUGGUUGAUGAAAGGGUGAGAAGACGUGCUCACUGGAAGUCACCCGCUGGAUCACUUAGGAAGCCGCAGAAGUGCCGAAGGACAUGCAUGUGUAUCUUUCAAAGUUCUCAACUGAUUUAUUAAAAAAAAUCAUAAAGCAGACUUUUGAAAAACCUGUUCAAUCUAUUCUUCUUUAACAGCUUUACUGAAAUGUAAUGCACACACCAUAAAAUUCACCCAAAGUAUACAAUUCCAUGUUUUUUAGUAUAUUGACAGAUACGUGCAACCACUACCACAGCUAAUUUUAGAACUUUUUUUAAUCUCAAAAAGACAUCUUGUACACCUUAGCUAUCACCCCUUUAUCUCCCCAUUCCCCUACAUGUACCCUUCAGCCUUGAGCAACCACAAAUCUACUUCUUGUCUCUGUCCAGCCCAAUUCCUCUAUUGUGGACUUUCGUAUGAGCAGAAUCACAUAGAAUGAGGUCUUUUGUGACUGGCUUCUUUUACUCUGUGUAACUGUCAUGGUUCAUCCAUGCUGUGGCAUGCGUCAGCACUUCCUUCCUUUUCAUGGCUGAAUAAUAUUCCAUCGCAGGGAUAGACCACAGUUUCAUGGAUCCAUUUGUCCAUUGAUAGACAUUUGGGUGGUCUCCACCUUUGGCUCUUAUGAAUGAGGCGGCCAUAAACGUUUGUGUACAAGCUUCUUUGGGUGUGGACAUGUGUUUCCGUUUCUAGGGUUAUGUUUUAUGAGACGUUUUCACUUUCUUCUAAUAAUAAGAUUCAUUUUUUAAACAACACUCUUUCCCUGGCCCUAGAAAAGGCUUUGUUCUUAGAUGGGAUCCCGAUCCCCCUGUCAGUGAUCCUGGCUGAGAUACUGAAUUGUCUGAAUUUUAGAGCUGGAAAGGCCUUCGGGCGAACGUGGUUCAGCCCCUUUUUAUAGAUGGGGAAGCUGAGGGCCAGAGAGGCCACACAUAAAGAGACAGGAUUGAAUACCGGUUUUUGGAGUUACAAUCCAAUUACUCCAAAAGUUCUCCCUAAACUCUUACUAAAACCCCAGGUUGCCUUCUUGACUGGCCUGGGGCAGCAGAUUAAGGUGGGUUGGGUGAACAGAUGGUGGUUAGCUUGCCCUCUUUUAUGUGAUUAUGGGUCAAGGUUUUCAGUCAUCCAAUGUACUCUUGCCUGUUUUCCUUUCACCCAUCUGUCUGUCCAUCCAAUGUCCAUCUGAUGUCCGAGGCCCAGAACAUCUCCCCAUCCACCAGCGGCCGAAUAAGAACAGCACCUUGUGGCGCCAGCAUCUUUCUAGUUCUUUCUCCCCUGCGGUGAUGGGCGGCCCGGCUGCUUAUCCGGGGAAUAAUUAAAUUAGGAACCAAUUCAGAGAAUGAAAUUUUAUCUGAUUUGGCCAAGCCCGUAAUAAGCAAGGGGCUGUAAUUGUGACUCCAGGAUACAUUAGGAAGUUGUUUUUUCAAGGGUACGCUGGGUGAAAGCAUUGAAAGAAAUAUGUGGAGACCAGGCCGGGAGAUCUCCCUGGGCCAGGUUUCUUGCAUGGCCUGGGGGUGUGGUCCCACAGGGCGGCUGUGUCCUCAGGCUGGUCCUUCCAGCGUUUAUGUUUCCAGGCACCAUUUAGCUCUGAUGAGGUAGAUAAAAGUGUUUUGUGGCUGGAGUGUUCUCUGUGCUUAGGAAAGUUCUGUUAAAAUCCUUAUGGAUAUCUAUCUCAUUGUUAUCACUGAUAUUCUAAAGCACCUUUACAACUGUAAUAAGAAGUAAACUUGGCAGAAACUCUGUGGCUAUAAAUCAGGGGUGCCGCUUUGCAACCCCCACGGAGCUUAUUGAAAGAAAUGCACAUACUUUGGUCCUACAUCAGCUGUUACAUCAAGUCUCCGGGGAUGGAUGCUGGGCAUUUGUGUGUGUGUGCACGCGUGUGUGUGUGCAUGCGUGCAUGUGUGUGCAUGCGUGCAUGUGUGUGCAUGCAUGGACCUGGAUUCGUUAAGCUCUUUAGCUAAGAAACGCUGAGGGAACUUAGCAGUGAUUGUAAUCAUUCUUCUAAUGAGAAUUUCCAGUUCUCCUAUGGCAAAGAUAAGGGACAGAUAAUUAGCACAGUGGUCUCAGGAAUGAGCCUCAUUUGUCCUCAAUCUGUGAUGAGACUUUGUGACUGUCUUUGAGUUUCAUGUUCAGAUUCCCUGAUUGUAACUAACACACAUUGUUCAUCACUUGGUAGCAGUGGUGGAAUUUUAGAUCUGUUUUUCUCUUGGGGAAGGACCCCAUUCUCAUCCCCACAGUGGCCCAGGCUGGAGGCCCAGGAGUCUCCUUUGACAGAUAGCUGGUCAGUGCAGAAUUGCUUCCUUUGUGUCUCUGCCACUGGAAGGUUAUCUGUUCCUUCAGAACAGGAAAUGUGUCUUAUUCAACGUGGCAUCCCCAGGGCCUAGUCCAUGGGAAAGAAUGAUUGGGCCGAUGGACAGACAGAUGGGUGAAAGGAAAACAGGCAAGAGUAUAGUGAAUAAUUGAAAACUUUGACCCAUAGUGCAGGGAUGGUGAGUGUCUUUCAGAUCGUCUGUUUAUAGCUGGGGAAACGGAGGCCUGCAGAAGUCAGUGACUUGCCCUAAUCCUUCAGCUUUGAUCAAGAAGAACAUUGGGGAGCCUGGCCCUUCAAUGUCUUCAACUCUUCUGACUCAGGCUCUGCACAUCCUCUUGAGAGUCACCCUCCAGUGAAAAGAACUCUUUAUUGAGGCCCUGCUGUGUACCCCAUGCUGUUCUAGGAGCUGGGGAUCUAGCAGUGAGUUAGACACACAGGGUCCCAGUGCUCACAGAGGGCAUAUCCUCAUGGAGAGAGACAGGCAGCAGACAAGGUCGCAAAUAUCAGAGAAUAGACAGGCAUAAGGGCCAUGUGCUGGAGUGACCAGCUGGUGUGCGGGAAAGGCCUUUCCACAAAGGUGACAUCUCCGUUGAUUCUUGAAUGUUCAGAGGGUGCUGCUGUCUGAUGCUUGGAAGGAGGGAACAGUCAGUGCCAGGACCCCAAGGGGAGAACCUGUUGAUGGGAUGGGAUUCAUUUAUGCUCGGGAGAAAGAGACUUGGUUUAUUGGACGCCUGGGUUGAUUUUCUUCUCUUCUGCAUCCUCUGCACUGACAUUUGCAGCUCUGCCUUCUCCCCGUCCCGUCUCUGGGUGAAGAACACCUGUCCGAUGCUCGCUGGCCUGCAGCUGCUGCAGAGUUUCAGAAAACAGGGCUAGCAAAAAACAAAGCAAAACCCCAACAUCCCUGUCCUCUCACUAAGGGCUUGGCUGGGGAGGCAGAGUUAUUUUUAUGUAAGCACAUGCUUGAGGGGGUACGUCUUGGGGUGGGCAGCUGAAACCACACUCAUAAAAACAAGACCGAAAUAGGACUGUGAAUUCCCAAAGGUGAACACAGGCCGUUAACUUGAAUUUGGUGACAGUUCCAUGCAGCCUAGGUCCUGGAGCGGGAACCCUUUGGAGGGGGAUGAGGCAUGGAAAACUGUUUGCUGAUUUGGCCUCUUCUUUAAGCAUUGCUUUCCGGCCCUGGCUGUGACAGAGACCUGGCCCUUGCUCAGGAUUUGAGCCCCCUCAAGGGGAAGUUCUUCCUCCCUCCUGGUGCUGCCUCCAGCUGUUUCUGUCUCCUCGUCAGUAAGAACCUCUGUUUCUUGAGGGCCCUCCUGUUGGUUGUCCUCUUGUUGCAGCCACCUCCCUACCUGCGAGGGAGUGGGCCCCAGGCUGCCUCUCCAUCCCAGGUCCUGCUGUUAACCUGGGUAACCGUGGUCUCCAUGGGGCAGCACUCUGGCCUCCCAGGUCCUGCAUCAGGACACCCUGAACCUUGUCUACUCCUGGACUGCUCCAUACCACAUGGAGUCCGUCCUUGUUAAUGACGUGUUAAUGCCAGGCUUUCUUGUGGAAACCACACCCAAGACACCAGCUGGUCAACCUGACACACAGUAGGGCCUCAACGGAUUGUGUCAUCAGUUAUUUUCAUAAACUUUAAAUCUCUUUCUGGUCUCCCCAGACAUCCUUAAGAGUGAUCCUUUGUCACAUUGCAAAGUUUUCCCAAUAAAUAUUGGUCAGUAGUUGUGACAGUAAUAUACAUCUCCAUUUUAUGUUGUUGACUAAUUUUUAAAUGGUGGACAAAACAUAAAUUUUUCUACAUUUUAAUAAAUGGAAAGAUAAAAGAAAUUUUUUUUUCUGAGUAGUUUGGUUUAGAAUCAUUCCAGUUGUUCAUUCAGCAUCUCUUCCCAAGUCACAUGAGUCCUACACCAGGCAGCUGUGGCUGUAUUGACAUGCUGAAUGCUUGCUCAGAGUCCCCAUAAUCUCUUGGCACUCCUAUAUGCUGCCUCAUACUUUUAUUUUAAUUUUUUAUUUUGAAAUAAUUUCAGACUCACAAGAAGAUGCAAAAAUAGUAGACUCCCUGUGUACCCUUCACUCAGCUUCCCACAGGGAGAACAUCUUAUGCAACCCUCAGACAUGAUCAAAGCCAGGAAACUGACACUGGUACAAUAGCAUUAACUGAGCUGCAGACCUUAUUUUUCUUAUUAAACCUAGGGAUCUACAGCAUUUUAGAAGCAUUUUAGAAUUUCAUAAGCUUUAGCAUUGUUGUUUGUCUUUUAGAGGAUGUUUCAAUCCCUUCCAAUUGACAAUCAGUUAAAAUUCGUUUCCGUAAGUUCAACAAAUACUGGAGGAUGAAUUUCACAGGUUCCACGGGUCCACAUGGCGCUCUAUGGGUGCAUCGUCUCUGAUGGGUGCACAGAGGUGACCUUCUACCUCAGAUCUGAGAGAUUCUGAGACAUAAAGAACCUUAGACAGUAGUUUGGUUUAUAGGACAGACCAGGGGAGCUGGAGUUCUGAUAAUGGAAACCAGGCUGCAUUGAGUAUUUAGUAUGCUUUAGGUUUUAUCUACUUUAUUUCAUUUCAUACACUCAGCAACCUUUGAGGUAGAUACAGUUAACAUCCCCAUUUUACAGAUGUAAGAACUGAGUUCAGAGGAGUUCACCCUGCCCACAUUCCUGCAGCUGGAUGGUAGAGUUGGGCGUGGAAUAUAGGCAGUGUGAAGUCAGAGACUGCUUGUUCUUAACCUUGCCGGGCUCCCUCCUUGGCUCAGGCCUGCACAGUGACUGCUGUGUGCCCUGGGGCUGUCCUGACUUCUCUGAGUCUCUGUUUCUUUACCUGCAAUGCAAGAGGCUUGUGUGAGAUCUGCCGUGUCCCUUCCAUUUCUGAGUGCAGGUGGUUUUAUUGGUGAAAACAAUUCUACCCGUAGAGCUAGAAACACCCAAGCAACAUCCAAAUGAAAUUUGUACCUUGCCCCUUGUAGGUGCUUUUAAGGUUGGUAGAAUUUCUGCAGCCUAGUUUGGUUUGAUGGGAGCCUCAAUUCCAAUUGAAUUAUGCUCUGGUGUAUUUUAAUUAAACCAUCUACAAGCUGAUUUUAUAAAGAGGCAGAAUCCCCAUGUAGUGAGCUGUGCCUGCCUCCCUCUGUGCUCAACUCUGGAGCCGAGUGAGGCUCGUAAUAACCAGAGGACUGUGCGAGCUGCUCAGGCUCGGCCUCAUGGGCAGCAUUAAUUGUGAGAUGCCACCGGAACGAGAUGCGAGGGCAUUAUCAGCAUAUACUUAAUUGAUUUUGCAUUCUCCACAAAGGAAGGUUAAAAUUAAGCUUGUUUGUAAAUGGUGUUUAAACUGCACAGGCUUGGGGAUGAGUUGCAGAAACUAACAGAGCAGGGCACUGGUUGGAGGGCCUAAUUUUCUCUUUAGGUGGUGGACAGAGCACAUCACUCAACUAAGGUAAAGAUUUUCCCAUUUAAAGGGGCUGAAAGAGUGUAAGCCUCGGCUCGUAAAUUUGACAGACAAGGCCUCCGCUUGAGUGCCUCAGGGAUGGUCUGGACUCUGGGGAUGAAUGUGUAAUCACAUUAGCGUGAUGAGUUAAAGGGCCCCAUAUUUUUAAAUCCUCAGGCAGAGCUGCAUUAGAGAAGAUGCUGUUCGAGAUCAGACUUAUGAUAAACAGGCUCAUGGAAACAGCCUUUGCUAUCCUCAUUCCUGGUAUAGAAUGUAAGAUUCUGAUUGUCAUUCUGACAUGCCCCAGGAAAGGUCUCUGCUCAAACCCAAGAUGAGCUUUAAACCUGAGGUGGAAUGCCGUUCUCUAAGUAUCUGUUCUUUGGCUCUAACAUAUACCAGGAAUGAGAACAGCACUCUGGGUGUGUUCUCACUCUCCUUUAAUCCUGAUAAGAAAACAUUUUAAGUAUCUCCAGAUCCAUCUAUAUAAUUUGCAAGACGCAGUGCAACAUGAAAUGCAUAUUAAAAAUUAUUAAGAAUUGGCCGGGCGCGGUGGCUCACGCCUGUAAUCCCAACACUUUGGGAGGCUGAGGCAGGUGGAUCACGAGGUCAGGAGAUUGAGACCAUCCUGGCUAACACGGUGAAACCCUGUCUCUACUAAAAAUACAAAAAAGUAGCCGGGCGUGGUGGCAGGCGCCUGUAGUCCCAGCUCCUCGGGAGGCUGAGGCAGGAGAAUGGUGUGAACCCGGAAGGCGGAGCUUGCAGUGAGCCGAGAUCGCACCACUGCACUCCAGCCUGGGCGACAGAGCGAGACUCCGUCUCAAAAAAAAAAAAAAAAAUUAAGAAUUUAAAAAUAGGGAAAGCAGAACAAUACAUUCUGUAUAGGGUGUUUCUGAGCAAAGGGCCCUGUGUGAUUGACCAUGGGUCCACGCCCUUGGAGUUGGCUCUGGGAUCUUGUAGGAUGCUGAUCCUAGACCAAUGUGAUUUAUAGCAACUUGUGUGAAUUGUGAACUCCCCGGGGGCACGGGCUGCAGCUGAAUCACCUUGGUGUGCUGGGAGGGGUCUGGCUGGAGGCCUGACCUAAGCACACGCUUAGGAAAUGCCCGUUGAGCUGAAUCAACUAACUCAUGGAGCCAUCAGCCUGGUCUGCUGGGGAAAUUUCAUGUGACUUUCUCAGUCUCCACGCAUCGGGAAUCUGGGACAGUCUACCGCUAGGCUCUUCAGAACAGACAGGGACAAGGACCAACAUUCUCUAAUGAAACUCACUGACUUGACAGCUCAGCUUUGAGAAGAGAAAACCUGAAUACAAAACCCAUCUACAUUAUGUGUGUGUAUAAGCCUCAAGUCCUGGUGAUUUUUCACUGUAAAAUGGAAAAGAUUGACACACAGUGGCUCUCCAGUACCUCUGUGUGGUUAAUGUGUGUGUCUGUCGUGACUCUGUGGCUCAGUCCCAAGAGAGGGGCAGCCCAUCUCCCCUGGCUUUUCAUCCCUGAUGUCCUCCCUGUGAGCUCUGCUCCUCCCAGUGGAGUAAAAUGCUCCUGGAGACAGUCUAGGAUUUUAGGGGCCACUGUAGGUCAUCCUUGUCAUUCUGGAUCCCGGAGAAUGCCACCUUGCAAAGUUGAGGGGGGCAUAGUGCAUCUUGGUAAGGAAAUAAAAUCCCGCCCAGGAAGCAUCUCUCCCUGGAGCAAGAGGCUUGGAAGGGCCCGGGACUCCUUUGUGCUGACUCUUUGUUCCUUCCCUGCAGGCUGGCCCAGACUCAGAGUUGCCCUUUCCCCUUUGCCAGUGGAGAGGGAGAGAGGAGCAUCCAGGGCCAGCUGCCAAAGACAGGGGAGGUUCUAACCAAGGAAAGCCCGGACUUUUCAGGUUUUAAAUUGGAAGAGGGCUUCUUGAAUGAGCAUUAAAGUUACUUUUUUAUUGGAAGGGAGUGUAGGGGGUGGAUGCUGUGCUCAGCAUACAUCAGGAGAGAGCUGCCCAAGUCAGAUCUCUUCCGAGCAGCGUCUUGGGGGAGAGACUGUGCACCACCGCUAGAUUUUCCUCCCUUUGUCCUCGGUUUGUACAGAGGUCACUGGAGAUGUGAGCUCAAAGGGAGCCGGGACGCUGUGCUCUCCUCUCAUUGUCACAAGUCGAUGGGCCUGAAUAGGCUGUGACACUUGAAGAAAGAAAGAAACCAUCCUUUAUACCUCCUGGCUGGGGAGAGACAGCAGGGCAGGAAGCCUGCAGUGCUGGAGGCCAAAGCUACUCCCAUGGAGCCUCAGAUGUGUGGAGGGAGGUCUGUGCUGUUCCUGGGUGUCUGGGAUUGUACCCUCCCCACCGUGGGGAUGCACAGCCUGUUCUUAACUUAUUCAGCAAAUAACAAACAGCACCUCCAUGUUCAAGCAAAAGCUGGCUUUAUUUAUUUUCCCCAUUAAGCUAUCCACAGUCAUUGUUUUCACUUUCAAAAGCAAAAUAAUAGGAAAAAACUUCACAGUAUUUGUAUUACCUGAUGUAGGAGUCUGAGAGAACUUGAAUAAUAAGUCUGGCUUAGAAGUAUUAGGGGAAAAAUCUUGAUACACAAAAGAGAAACAGAAACAUGAAAAGAGGAAUGUGCUGAAACAGUCCUCCCUGCAAAACAUCAUUAACUCCGCGGGGGCUGGGAGCCUGUCUGUCUUGUCCACACACUGCACCCCACUGCCUAGCACAGCCGCAUUCAAAAGGAAAGUCAGCCCUGGCUGCUGGGAGGCAGUGGCGAGUGAGACAUGCCCAGGUCCUGUCCUCAUGGAGGUUAGAGUCUAGGAGGUGAAUGAGGUGGAAACACUUAGGCAAAGGAUCAUUUAAUUUCAGUUGUGAUGAGCUGGGGACAGGAACGGGAAGUGGUCUAUGAGCAAGUUUGCUGAUGCCGUGAGCCCAGUCUGGCAGAGGCGCGGGGUGCAUUGGAGAGCUCCAGGUCAUAAUGGAGGAAGCUGCGCGGAGGGAGAGGAGGCAGAGACUGCAGACGUGGCGAAGGUGUUGGGUGUGCAGGGGGAUGUUAUGUAAGUCCCCAGUGAGGUGCCUGGACCCAGAGUUCUCAUUUUAAGGCUUAGAAUGUGCUAGAAUCCUUGUUUCUAGAGACUGGAUUGAUGAUCACAACUGGGCGAUGCUCCCAACUAGGCCCCCGCCCCUACCUGCCACCUGAAUUGUGCCCUUUGCAGUUGGGUGGCACACUGUUUAGUGUCUCCUGCUCACUGCCUCCAGGGUUCCAGGGACUUGCUGAUUUUCUGUCUCUACUGAGAGAUUUGAGAAAUUCUUGAAGCAACUUGCCAAGUAGAAACUGUCUAAUGGCAUCAGUGCAAGGGUUCGGUGUCUUUCCCAGCCGGGGGGCACUGGCCCUGCAGAAAUGAAGUGGAAAGAUCUUGGGAGGGAGAGCAAGCUACCUUCCCUGGGGGUGCAGCAGGCGUGACUUGAGCUUGCGCUAAUCACACCCACUUCUGUCCUGAGAAAGUCUUCUAUGGAAAGAGGCUAAAAAGACUAUGUGGAAAAUAUCUCUUUUAAAGCCCCCAUUUGAGACCUCUCCCCUGCCCUGUGUGUGCCUAGCCCGUAGGUUGCUGCCAAGGUGAGCAGGCCCGGGAUGUGGCUGGGGAAGAUCUACAGCCUCCUGGCCGAGUCCACCCAGGAGGAGCCAUUUAAGACCCUGGAAACCCAUCAGACCUGGCAACUGGAGGUCAUUAGCCGUCUGACUGAGAGGCGGGUCGUAAAAUAAGCCCUAAGUGGUUACGAGCUCUGUUAACCAUUUUAAAAUGCACAAACAGAGGAGCUUUGGUUUGGCGCCUCUGAAAGGAAAUGGGCGUCGUCUGAUGGGAGAACAUUCGCCUUCAUGGUCAAGGCGCAAGGACCAGCCUGCAUUGGCUCAUUCAUGCGCCUGUCGAAUGGUUGCUGUGCCCUUUGCCUCUUCCUUGGUUUCUGAUGGGGCAGAAACUUACCACCAUGUAUCUAGCUUUCUUUUUUUGGUGAACUUUUAAGGAAUUGGAGUAUAACCUUCAUGCAUUAAAGAGCAUCUAUCCUAAGUGUGCUGCUUGAUGGAUUUUCACAAACAGAACUCACCUAUGCAACCAGUACCUAGAUCAGGUAUACAGACAGCACCCCAGGACCCCUGGGCUCUGUUCUGGUCAUUAACCACCUCUCAGCACCCAUGCAAGGGAAAUUGCUAUCCUGACUUCCGCGGCCUGGGUUUUUGGCCUGUUUUGUGCUGUCUCUAACUGGAAUCCUGUGUGGUUCUCCUUUAUAUCUGGGUUCUUUUGCUCAGUACUACAUCUGUGAGAUUCUUCCCUGGUGAAGCUUGUCCAUUUUCGCAGCUGAAUUGUAUUUGUCCGUUCUACUGUGGGUAGACACUGUGUGAUUUCCAGUUUUUGGCCCUACAAAUAGUACAAUGAACAUUCUAGUUGAUGUCUUUUGAUCAGCAUAUGGAUGCCUUUCUGUUGGGCACGUAGCUAGGAUUGGAAUUGUGGUCUUUGGGAGUGAGUACGCCCAAGCUUCAGUAGAUAAUGCCAGUGUUCCAAACAAUUGUACUCAUUUACCGUUCCCAUCAGCAGCGUAUGAGUCUCUGGAAAGAUGAAAUAAGAGCCUGGAAAAAAUGUAAGGUGAGACUGACUCCCUUUUGUCCUCUGCCCAAGUUCCCAAAAAGAAGAGACCCUGGGGGAUAACAGCUGGCCCUUUUUGCAUUGAAUGGGUGCACUGGAAGAGAUAAGGCUUCUGGGAUGCCCCAGAAAGAUGCACCUGUCCCUCCUGGGGUUCUGCCCACGUGGUCACGUUUCACUGGAAGCCAGUCUGUUUCUGAACUUGCGGAUGGGGUUGGUUGGUCUCUGAGAAGAGCCCAGAAUUCAGCAUUUUAGUCUCCAUGCUUUGGGUGUCUGCAUGCAAUGAAGCAAAGCCUCCAGGCUCAUCUUUGAGAUGAAAGUGGCUGGCCUGGUGGCUGGCCUGGUAGCUGGCCUGGGUUUUCUCUUGGGAGGGCUUGAGAGCUGCCACCAUUUAAUGGCUCAGUCAAGAAAGGUUUUUAUUUGUAGAUCAGUCCAGUCUCAGAACCAAAUGGUUCUGCACCCACCCCCUGGACUUCCAACCCAGUGUUCUAGGUGGAGAAAGAGCUUUCCCUGUGCCAAAAGCUGUUGUUUGGUGUGAUGAGGGGUCCAGAGCAGUGGGAAGAGGCAGCUGACAUUUACUGAGCCUCCUGCAUGCUCAGGAGAACUCCGAAUGCAGGUGUGCUGGUCUCCCCAACCACACAGGAAGUGGAAGAAGAGAGGACUCUGCACUGUCCCUGAGCAGCAGAGCCCCAGCUGGGGUGUGUGUCCUGCCCUGGCUCUGUCAAAUUUGUAACUCACAACAGUGGCAGUGGCUGGCUAAAGGAGACUUGGAAGGAAGGAAAACCUGUGCCCGGGUUAUUGCCCGGCUGUCUUCCCUACCCCAAGUAGAUUCAGUAAAUCGGGGGCAGGGCUUGGAAGCUGUUGGUAACAAAUGCCUUAGGUGAGUUUUACUCAAUUUGGGGAAGCAGUGACUUCCCAGACCCUUUUGAUGAGAGGCUGGGUAAGGAGAGGAAUGGAGGAAAUAAGAAACAGAUCUCACGCUCCAGGAGCGCCUGGCCUGAGCAGCCUCGUGCAGGAAGCUCUCUGAGGAGCUGGACAAGCUCUGUGUCUGCUGCUCCACAGGGUCAUGCUUGAAAUGUGACUAGGACGGCCGAAGAAUGGAAAUUUUACAUCUCAUUUACUUUUAACUAAUUUAAAUUUAAAAGCAGAUACUUAAUUCAGUUAUUAGAAAACUUUUAAGAAUGUUUGGAACAGCUUGGGUCCAUAACUCCUUUUCCGACUCUAAGUCUUAUGAAAUCUAGAUACAGCUCAGGUACUUCAGAUGAAAAUGUAGCAUCCAAAUUGAGAUGGACCUAAGUGUAAAAUACACACUGGAAUUUGAAGACUUAGUAUGAAAAAAAUGCAAAUUUUUAAUUAAUAACUUUUAUACUGACUACAUGUUGAAGUGGUUAUUUUGCGUCUAUUCGAGUUGAACUACAUGAAAAUUAACCUCACCUGGAACAUUUAACCUAGGUAUGGGCUCACACUCUGUUUUUGUUGGGCAGUGCUGCUCUGAGGCACUUUCUUGCUGGAAUUUGACUCAGAGUGCUAGGGAGUUGGAGGAGAGGAGAGAAGCCCCAGCUGUGGCCCCUUGUUUGGCUCACGUGGGAGCAGGGUUUCAGGCUGAUGGCACACCUGGCCCUAUAGAUGGCCACAAGGCCACCUGUGAUGGGUCUGUUGGGCUCUGGCUGGCCUGUCCAUCUCCUUGGGUACUUUGCCCAAAGAGGGAAACUGCCCGUUCCCUCCAGGUAGUGCCUUUAGAAAACGAGAAUCUUCUCUAACGCUCUGGGCUAGGAAGAGAGAGCUGAGCACGUCUCACCCUGGGCUGCACUGCAUCUCACACAAGUGGGACAUGGCCUGCUGCUGGUCAGGGUGAGAACUCUGCCUUUAAGUUAGAAUCAGAUCAAAUCAAAUCAAAUUGAAUUCUUUACCCCAGUGGGGUAGAGAGCACCGCCAAAUACUAAGCUACAGGAAUGUGGCCCAGAAAGCAAAUUAGGUUUUAUUUCUGCCUCCUGCCUUUGCCCCGCUGUUUCUGGAAGAGACCCCAUAGACAGUGCCGUGAAGGGCAGCCUACGGAGUCUGUGGCAGGCAGGGACUCGCAGGUGAGCCUGGUAGUGGGUCGGCGGGUUCUCAUCCAUGGUGCUCAGCCCGUCUGAGGUCAUCUGCCCUCUUCUUCAUUGGAUUCUGGAAGCCUCCCCACCAGCCUGCGAGAUGCAGCUGAACAGGGACUUGUUUUGUUUACUGCUGCAUCCCAGGGCUCUACACUUGAGCCUGACAUAGAGUAGGGCUUUAAUAAUCUUUAUUGAGGGCCGGGCACAAUGGCUCACUCCUGAAUCCCAGCACUUUAGGAGGCCCCGGCCAGACAGAUCACGAGGUCAAGAGAUCAAGACCAUCCUGGCCAACGUGGUGAAACCCCGUUUCUAUUUAAAAAAAAAAUCAGCUGAGCAUGGUGGUGUGCACCUUUAGUCCCAGCCACUCAGGAGGCUGAGGCAGAAGAAUCUCUUGAACCUGGGAGGCAGAGGUUGCAGUGAGCCGAGAUCGAGCCACUGCACUCCAGCCUGGUGACAGAGCGAGACUCAGUGUCAAAACAAAAACAAAACAAAACAAAAAAACUUUACUGAAUGGGUUCAUUUGGAGGAUGCCCCUUAAAUCUGAUGGUCAAAUAUGGCCUUCAUGUUGACCUUCCUGAAGUGACAUCCCCGUAGGUGGGCAUAUGCAUUUCCCUUGGGAGAGAUUCCCAGAGGGGCCUCUGGCUUGGGAUUGGCUAGGAACCUCAGACCUACAUUGUGUUUUUACUCUAGAUCUGUAAGUGCAGAUUUUUCUUUUUUUUCCAGAAACUGUUUCUUGGACAACACAGCAACUACUUUCCAUUGCAAAGAAAAAUCCUGUCCUUUGUGUGCUCUCUACAAAGCACUCACACAGCCAGGCUAUAUCAUUUGUUCCUGACAACGUGCUGGGGGGGACAUCACCAUUUUCUGCAUGUCCCCAGGAAAUGGGCGGGACCACUUGUCCAAAGUCCUACAGCUAAAGGGAGGCACAGUGACACCUUAGAUUCAGGGGAACUCCCAUCUUGGGGUGACUUCUUUGCCCUCAGUAUAUUCCACAUGUCAUGGAACCUAAUGGAUAAAUCUGGUUUGGUCAGGCCUGGAGCGCAGAACUGUUAAAGGCAGGCAAUGAGAGAAAAAUCUGCGUCCUUCCUCGAGGGAUGAGCUGGCUGACUGGGAAGGUCCAGGCUCAGGCUGGCCUCUGCCCAGGUGUCCUAUGGCAGGGGCUCAUGGAGGAGCACUGUUCCUGUUUUCUGGGUCCCCUGCUCUGCCUCACCUGUUUAAAGUCAGUGACUCAAAUUUUUAAAACUGUGAAACCGUAAACUGUCCAUCCCUGUUCAGCCUUCCCCAGGCCACGGGCCCUGCACGUGUCACUGCUUGUUCAUGGUUCUCCCCUGUGUUGCCUUUGAGGCUCACUCAUCUUGAUGACUCAGAGACUUGCCAGAGACCCUGGACUCCCCGUCCCAAAUUCCCCGAGCCUGGCCCCGAUGAUUCUUGCAAUGUUACUCUGUUCAUGGUGCCUCUGCCCCAUUUCCAUCUGUGCCAUAUCACCAAUAGUUGGGGGGGGGGUCCCCCAAACAACAGGGACUAACUUGAACUUUGCAAGACUCUUGAAUUUCCUGGCUAUAUUUAUUAUCUGUAUGGCACUGAUUUGUACUAGAGCUGAGCCUGCAGAAGUCAGUUGAACCCAUCCUCUCUAUAUUCAGGAGGACUACAGGAUGUAGGAACUCAAACGGGAUGUUGAUCUGUGGGAGUUUGCAACUUUGCCUAGCAGCACAGACCUGCCUCCUUGGGAGAGGCCUCUGGGGAGGGAUGCUAAGCCGAUGGAUGUCUGUGCAGAGACAAGGGACUGUCCUUUUCACCUGAGAGGCCAUUCUCAUCCUGCCUAGUCCUGUCUGAUUCACAUCUGACCCCAGCUUAGCCCAGACAGAGACAUGCUAAAGCAUGUUCUGAUACUUUCUAGCUUCGAUUAUCUCCUUGUAUGCUUUCUUUGUAUACUUAGGGCCCAAAAUACCAUAAGGUGGAACAUUCUAAAGUAAAAAUGAUCCCCUUUUUAUUGUUUGAAAAUUUGUGUUUCUUAUUAAAAUAGAACAUUUUACAGUUAUUCACAAGAUAAGGUCUUACUUUAAAAAUCACUAUUUUCCUCUGUCUUUCUGACUUCUUUUUUUAAUUCAAGAACAGGGAUAUUAAGGCAGGUGAUGAAAGCAGAAUUUUUAAUAAGAGCAUAGUGAUGCUUUUCACAACGGACUUAGAAGACAUUAAAAUAUAUGUGUUUUGAUCUUUUUCUGGAUUUGAAUAUGAAGGACUAGUUAUUGCAACAGACAGCAAAGUAAUUCAUUUCGGAUGCAUUUCAGCAAGCCAGCCCUCUAGGAGACGCUGGAAUAAAAUGUGGAAGUGUGUGACACAGACCAGACUGGACAUGUACCCGGCCCAUCAGCUAAAAAGCCAAAGAGCAGGUGGAAACAGGAAUAACAGUGACAGUGAUGGUUACCAUGAUGAGGAGCACUGCCAACGAUUCCUGAACUUCCCAGGUGCCCUGUCCUUGCUUGGUGCUUCCCAUGGAUUAUCUCAGUCUUCCCUGUGGCUCCAUUAGACUACAUAUUGUCACAUCAUCCCCAUUUUUCAGAUAAGGAACUGAGGUGGGCUAAGUGUCAGGCCGUGGAGCCAGGAUGAGAACUCCAGCUGUCUAGAUAACCCAUGUCCUGGUAACUGCCACUCUGCUCCCGAGUGGUCAGCAUGUAAACCACUGCAGCGUGGGGACUGACUUCACCAUCCCCUUGGCUCUGCCUCUGACCCCCCGAGCAGGUGAGAGCUCGAGCCAGCUAUUCCGGGAAUUAGGCAUAUACUCAUUUUUUGCUUCAGUUAUUUCACUAAUUAAGGCAAAGUUUCUGGUAGUUUGACAUUACGUAUCUGGAUAAUUGCCUCAAUGUAUCAUUUUCACUUUGCACCCGCAGACACAACCUUUAAUGAAACUUGAAAACCCAACUCUCCUUGGGGGAAAUGAUACUCACUUCUGUUUCUAGGCCAGGCGCAGUGGCUCCCGCCUGUAAUCCCAGCACUCUGGGAGGCCGAGGCCAGCGGAUCACGAGAUCAGGUGUUCGAGACCAGCCUGGCCAACAUGGUGAAACCCCGUCUCUACUAAAAAUACAAAAAUUAGCGGGGCAUGGUGGUGGUCGCCUGUAAUCCCAGCUAUUUGGGAGGCUGAGGCAGGAGAAUCGCUUGAACCCAGGAGGCGGAGGUUGCAGUGAGCUGAGAUCAUGCCACUACACUCCAGGCUGGGUGACAGAGCAACACUCCGUCUCAAAAAAACCAAAAACACAAAAACCAUCUGUUUCUAAAUCUGUUUCUGAAAGUAGUUGAGGGCGCAGACUUCCACUUAUAAGCUUAAUUGCCCAACAUGCAGAAGAAGUCUCCAACUUCCCUGUUUAUCAGGCUUGAAAGUCAGCCUUGGUUUGGGGCAGAUGGCCUGCUCCUGGUCCUUAUCUGGGAGAUGAGAGGUUCCGACAGUGUGAUCUCUCAAGUGCCUCAGUUUGGAUCUGAGCUUCUGUUCUAGCGGCUUCCAUGCCCAACUGGAUUGCAUAUCUUAGGAAGCAGGACAGAAGUGCACCUGCACUGAUUACUGAGCAAAUUGGUCUGAAUAAGUGCAGUAGAUGCCAGAGAUUUCCACGAAUGAUGUGAAUGUGAUCACUGGCCAGAAAAUAUCCAUGGACGAUAAAUAUCUGGGCUUCAUGCUCUGAAAAAUGUUCCUAAUCUCUUCUUUGUGAUCCCCAAAGAGAUUUUUAAGGGAGUUUGGAAGUCUGCCACUUGCAGAAGUCCUGGUGUUCCCAGCACUAAGUGCAGGAUGUGGAGUCUGGGGUGCGACUGUCUUGUCACUCAGAUGGGGCUGCAUGCCCGGCACAGUGCUAAGUGCAGCCAGUUACUCUGGAAUGUGCAAAUGGCCCCUCUGCCCCAGCUGCAGAGCGCCUUGCGGGUGGCUCAGGUCCUAGUGGGGAUAGGAAGAAUGGGACAAAAGGAGGAGGCUAAGCCCAAGGCAUGUGCUGUCACCAAAAGUGCUGGCUUCAUCUCAGAAAGCUGUGGCUGGGUUGGGCUUGGUUGCUCAGGGGAACAGGGAGACGCAGCCCAGGAAAUGAGCUGUGGCUGGGCUGGAGCCCACCUCCCCAGGAGGGAGGUGCAUGGCAGCCCAGGUGGGGUGCCCCCAUCCUAAGAUGAAAGGUCUCCACCUCUUGCUUAAAUUGUAAGGUGAACGCUUUUGGCCAUUUCUAAGGAAAAGCACCUUUGGGAUUUGUUCAUCAUCCUUCAUUUUUGCUCAAGGUUUUGGGUGUGAAAACCUCAGAAAAACUAAGUCAACCAAAGACUUUCCAGCGAUGUCAUCGACUGUGUUGUCAUCCAAAGGGGAAAAUAAUCCCAGCUUAUGAAUAUUUAGAAAGAAGAUAAUUGCAAAUUGCUUUGUGACCGUGUAAACUCGUUUUUUUUUUUCUUUCCCCCAGCCAGUUACAUAAGAGGAGGUGUGGGUCAGUCCCAGAAAUAGAUGCAGAAGCAGUGACAGAACACGUCUUGGCGGUGGUGGAGAGAGACAGCCCUGGGUUCGAGUCCCAGACUCGCAGUGUGUUAGCUAAAGAAGUUUGAGAAACAUCCGUCUCUUUCUUUCCAUUUCAGCCUCCUCCCCCUUCCCCUAGCUGGUCGACGCUCAAAGCUCUCCUAGCCCAACACUCUGUAACUUGAGGAAUAAUGUUUUAAACCCCCAAAUCUAGUCCUCCCAUAAAACCCAGUGAAUCUCUCAAAUUGAUUAAAUGGAGGCACUCAUUUUAUUAGAUAGGUAACUGGUAUUUUGCCUUUUCUGAAGGGUAGAAGAGGGGAAAAAGUGACUGAGGGGACCAAAUAAGAAAAAAAAGACAAAAAGACAGAAGAAUUCGGGUUUUUAGUUGAUUCCGAAUACUCGAUGCUUUUGAAACGUUUCCAAGUUUCCUUUACGGGAAAGGAAUGCAAAUGAUCCAAAAGGGAGGAGGGAUUUUUUUCCCCCUUCUUUUUUGUCCUGAGCUCAGUACCUGGGAUUUUGCGGCAUGUGCUGAAAAAUUAUAUCUUCUGGGUGCAGAAAUUUGCCUGAAAGGGUUAUACGAAACUGAGAAUGGGUCAAAACAAAACAAAACGGAAAAAACAAGACUUCUGGCCACAGGAAAUCUGGCAUUUUUUAAAGUUUGCGCCCCACAAAGAGGAAAUAUUCCAAAGGUACUCAGGAUGUAAAAGGGGAGAUCUUCACAGAUGCCUCCGUGGAUGGCAUGGCAAUCCAUCCAUCAAUGAGAAGACCAUGAUUUCUUUUAAUUUUCUGUGUGUUUCCACAUUCCCCAGUGAGAAUUCUUCCACCUUUUUUUGUGCCAUGGGAAAAACCUGAAGGGCAGGCAGAGCUGCUCCCGAACUUGUGACCUUCUCUGAGGUUGCAGCGGCUCUUGUAGAACAUGACUCUGGGACAUCACUUCCUUUUGUUUUCUUUCGGAGCUGAACCAAAGAAUGUGCACCCUCUUUCUCUAGUGCUGUGGUGUCUGCUUAUUUUUGUAUUUGUGCUUUCCAUCCAUCUUCUGUGAUCACAAGGCAUUCUUAAGGUUUUCUAGCACGACUUGCGGACAUCCAGACUCGUGGGGGGCCCACCCAUGGCUCGGUAAGCCAGCAGCCCAGGGCACUGGCACUACCAUGAGGCACUGCAUUAAUUGCUGCAUACAGCUGUUACCCGACGGCGCACACAAGCAGCAGGUCAACUGCCAAGGGGGCCCCCAUCACGGUCACCAGGCGUGCCCCACGUGCAAAGGAGAAAACAAAAUUCUGUUUCGUGUGGACAGUAAGCAGAUGAACUUGCUUGCUGUUCUCGAAGUGAGGACUGAAGGGAACGAAAACUGGGGUGGGUUUUUGCGCUUCAAAAAGGGGAAGCGAUGUAGCCUCGUUUUUGGACUGAUAAUAAUGACCUUGGUAAUGGCUUCUUACAUCCUUUCUGGGGCCCACCAAGAGCUUCUGAUCUCAUCACCUUUCCAUUACGGAGGCUUCCCCAGCAACCCCAGCUUGAUGGACAGCGAAAACCCAAGUGACACAAAGGAGCAUCACCACCAAUCCUCUGUAAAUAAUAUUUCAUACAUGAAGGACUAUCCAAGCAUUAAAUUAAUUAUCAACAGCAUCACAACUAGGAUUGAGUUCACGACCAGACAGCUCCCAGACUUAGAAGACCUUAAGAAGCAGGAGUUGCAUAUGUUUUCAGUCAUCCCCAACAAAUUCCUUCCAAACAGUAAGAGCCCCUGUUGGUACGAGGAGUUCUCGGGGCAGAACACCACCGACCCCUACCUCACCAACUCCUACGUGCUCUACUCCAAGCGCUUCCGCUCCACCUUCGACGCCCUGCGCAAGGCCUUCUGGGGCCACCUGGCGCACGCGCACGGGAAGCACUUCCGCCUGCGCUGCCUGCCGCACUUCUACAUCAUAGGGCAGCCCAAGUGCGGGACCACAGACCUCUAUGACCGCCUGCGGCUGCACCCUGAGGUCAAGUUCUCCGCCAUCAAGGAGCCACACUGGUGGACCCGGAAGCGCUUUGGAAUCGUCCGCCUAAGAGAUGGGCUGCGAGACCGCUAUCCCGUGGAAGAUUAUCUGGACCUCUUUGACCUGGCCGCACACCAGAUCCAUCAAGGACUGCAGGCCAGCUCUGCAAAGGAGCAGAGCAAGAUGAAUACAAUCAUUAUCGGGGAGGCCAGUGCCUCCACGAUGUGGGAUAAUAAUGCCUGGACGUUCUUCUACGACAACAGCACGGAUGGCGAGCCACCGUUUCUGACGCAGGACUUCAUCCACGCCUUUCAGCCAAAUGCCAGACUGAUUGUCAUGCUCAGGGACCCUGUGGAGAGGUUGUACUCAGACUAUCUCUACUUUGCAAGUUCGAAUAAAUCCGCGGACGACUUCCAUGAGAAAGUGACAGAAGCACUGCAGCUGUUUGAAAAUUGCAUGCUUGAUUAUUCACUGCGCGCCUGCGUCUACAACAACACCCUCAACAACGCCAUGCCUGUGAGGCUCCAGGUUGGGCUCUAUGCUGUGUACCUUCUGGACUGGCUCAGCGUUUUUGACAAGCAACAGUUUCUCAUUCUUCGCCUGGAAGAUCAUGCAUCCAACGUCAAGUACACCAUGCACAAGGUCUUCCAGUUUCUGAACCUAGGAGUCAGAGCCGUGUGGCUGAGUUUUGGCUGCUGAUCAUGGAUGCUGGGCCCCUGGGGCAUGAGCGCCUGCCCUCAGCCUGUGGAUACCAGCCCCCCCAGGGGCCUGAGAGUCACUUUGUGGUGACAGGCCACACUGCUGACUAUGGUGAUGGCUGGCAGAGGCAUGUGCUGGCGGAGCGAGUGCUGCCCAUGUGGACGGGGCACCGAGGGAUGGCUUGAAAGGCUGAGCAGGCUCGAACAAGCCGCCCUCCUUCCCAGAACGCCUCCUGCAGCCCUGACUAAUGGUCUUGCCCGGGAACUUGGUUAAUUGAGUAUUUCUGAAAAUAUAUCUGCCUGCCACUGGGACUUGGGCCUCUUUGAUCAUUUGAUUUUGUUUCUCCUUUUUUUGGAGUUUGAUGAGUUCUUUCCCUUCCAAGGCUUAGAAUCAUCUUUCUUUGAUUUGACCACAUGUUGACUCUGUCCCAUUAAUGAGCUUGUCUUUUGUCCCCAAGAUGGAUAGUAAGGCCAAUUCUGUGUUUCAUAUGGCCCUAGGAUGCUGGGACAUGCUUUUUCUGUCUAUGGGCUAAGGACUUUGGCCAGAUCCCAAGAGCCCCCGGUAAAGAGGCUUGAGCAGUGAUGGGUUACACCAAGAAGCUGUGGCCCAGAGGGCGGGGCGUUGGGGUCGCAGCCCUUGCUGUUCUGUUUCAGGGCCUCUCACUCCAGAGGGCGGGGCGUGUGCGUGACUGACAGCCCCUCCCGGCCUUUUCCAGGGCCUCUCCUCACUCCAGAGGGCGGGGCGUGGCGGUGACUGACAACCUCUGCCAGCCUGUUCCAGGGCCUCGCCUCACUCCAGAGGGCGGGGCGUGGGGGUGACUGACAGCCCUUGCCGGCAGGCCUCUUCUCCCUGAUCUCCUUGCUGCAGAUGGAGGUUCAGCCAGUGGGGGCUCUGGGCACAAGUGGCCUCCUCCCAGCCCUCCUCCCUAUGGCCACUUCACAGCAAGACGCACAGGGUGAAACUGUGCAGGCCCAGGGACCUUGGCAUGAGCAGCCUGAAGUAGAAACGAUGAUGGCGGAAUUCCAGAGGGCUGCUGAGCAGGAAAACCGAAACCCGUGGGCUGUGCUCGGCAGGCCGCACGUUCCUCCAAGGACGGGCUGACACCCAUGGAGAGCAGCCCACCAAGGGCAAUUGGAAGGGAAUCCUUGAGGUCAGCCUUAGACGCUGUAUCAUCAUUAAAUGCCAGCUGGGCUCCCCCGAGGGUGGGCAUCCUGCACCCGCCGCAGAAUUUCUUCGCAAUUUCCUGAUGGUGUUUCCACCUUCCUCCCUCAGUGCUUCCAAAAUGGAUCCAGCCAAAGAAUUUUAAUCCCUAAAUAUGUUCUCUUAAAGGAAACUCCUGUCUGAAUACGAAGCAUAGCUGGGAUUUUUGCAAAGUCCCUUUUACUUCCUGCCAUGCCUCCUGCCUUACGGGACUCGUCUUCUUUUAUUCUAGGGCCCUUAAGUGAGAAGCAGGAGGCUUUGAUGACCAAGAGCCCCGCAUCCAAUGCACGGCGUCCCGAGGACCGGAACCUGGGGCCCAUGUGGCCCAUCACACAGAAGAUUCUGCGGGAUUUCUACAGGCCCUUCAACGCUAGGCUGGCGCAGGUCCUCGCGGAUGAGGCGUUUGCGUGGAAGACGACGUGAGAGCUGAAUUGUUGCUGCACGUGCUGGGCCCGCCAAUGCCGUCAUCAUCAGGAUUUUACAAAUCUCUUUGCGGGGAACUGUUUCACUCAUGGUAUGGAAAACCCCAGGACUCUGCCACUCUAGGCACACAUGAAUUAUAACCAUUUUGGAAUUUCCUUCGUGAUGUUCGAGAGCUCAGCAAUGGACCCCUCACAGAGCUCCUCUAUCCGAGGCCAUUGGAGACCCCAGUUUCUCAAGAAUUCAGCUCUGCUCUGAGCGUCCUGGAGCUUGGGGAUGCAGCCAGCUGGCCUGCACUGGGUGUGGAGAGAACACCUAGGGAAGGCAGCCUGGCCCUGCCCGCCUCCGCCUUCUGGAGAGCCUCUGGGUUCUGAGUCAGCAAGCCAGAGGUCAUGCCACAGGCCUGGCUGGAACUUACACUUCACGUUCCCUUUUUUUCCCCCUAGAGAUGGGGUCUCGCCGUGUUGCACAGACUGUCUGUAUUCAAUGGCUAUCUUCACAGGUGUGAUCAUACCACAUUCACUUCUGAAACACUCUUGUUGCGAUCGCUAACCUCACUGGGACAGAGAACCGCAGUCUUUCGAGAAUGGAGGCUCUUCAUUUUUUUUUUCUCCUUUACUCCAAACUCAGCCCUCCAGUUUCUUCAGAUGUAAACCCUGUUAACGUCACUGUUUCCAAAAGGAAAAAAAUAAGUCAGUUUUUGGCAGCACCUUCAUCUUUCUGACCUCCUCCUAUUCUGUCCUUGUGGACUUAUGUUUAACAUAGAAAAUGAAUGCGUUUAAAACAAAACCACUUUCUGCAUUUAACCAGUCCUGGCUCUCUCUCUGCUGCCUCUUCAUACGUUUUCUCAAGAACUUCAGUUUAUAAUUGGAAGAGAAAUUUUUGCUGUUAAUGCCAGAAUGAGCAACCUCAAGGAAUUGAACACUUCUUGGAAAAUCUAGGUAAUUCAAGCCCUCAUCAGGUUUACAAGAUCAUCAGAGAAACAGAGGAUUUUAAUUUUUAGUUCUGGCCGGCUACAGGCUCCAUUUCUCUGCCUUCCCAUUGGAAAUAGUUUAUUUCCACAUUCUCCACUGCGUGUGGUCAAAGUUCCUCACCCAGCAAGGGACUAUAGAUACUCGUGUCCCAAUUCCAAAACACAAUGCACAAGCUGAACUUGGGCUGAACGUGGCGUGUUGAGAUUUGGAAUGAGGUUUCUAAGAGCCGUGUUCUUCAUGGAAUUUUCCAGGCCACUUGGCAGCUUGGUUUACCGAUGGAUGGGCUAGAGAUCUUGUCGUUUCUUGGAAGUCACAGGGAAGAUUGAAGAGAACGCUUGAGCAUCCUUGGCAACAGCCCAGGUGGGACCUGGAUGAAGCUUUGCACUCAAGUAUUGUCAAGGGAAGCUUCCUGUGAACCAAAGUUCUCAGGCCAAGGUCUCGCCCACCAAAGCCAGAAAGUGCAAGCACCCGUCUACCCAGCUCUAACUUGUAUGUGUGAGACAGACCAGGCUUCGGGGGUAGGAGGAUCUGCAGUUGUUCAGCCGUCUUUCUGCUGGUGUUGUCUUUCUGCCAUCAGAGAAGGGACACACAGCCCGUUCGAAGGUGUGCAGAGGGCUCUGAGCGCCAGGAUGGCCAGGGCUGUUUUUGCUACUGAAGGAGCGUGUGUCCUGAACUCCCACUUGCAGGGACAGUCCCCACCUUCUCUAUAGCCGGCACUGGGAGCAGCCGCCAGCAGGGAAAUCUGGCCUGAGCACAAGGAUGCUUUAGGGAGAGAUCACUUCAGUGUGUGUGUAUAUUUAUUUGCAGUACAGUGCGCGCGUGUGUGUGUGUGUACGCGCACGUGUGGGUGAGUGCGUCUUCUGAGUGGGUUCUGUUCAGUUGCUAAUGAGGCUCCUCCGCUCUGGACACAACCCUUUUAUAGAUUAAUUUCUCUGCCAAUUAACUUGUCAUUUUCAGUACAUAUUUUACUAUUCCACACCAACCAUAAUUACAACAAGGGAUUUUUCUUAUGCACUCCUAUGCAUGUGAAUAACAUGUGGUGUAAUUCUGCUUCUUACAGAAGUAUUACUGAAGGUAUUAUUUCCAAUAUUAUUUGGUUUAUUAUGCGGAUCUUUUUUAUAUAUGCAGUCCCAUCCCUUCUGUGCCACUCAAUGCCAUCCAGACAUGGUUUUUCCCUCCAGGGGCCUUUCUCUCCAGAGGGCACUUCGGCUGCCUCUGCUUCCUCUCAUUCGAGGCCCGGCUCUUGCUGACAGAAUAGGUUCCGUUCUGGGCGGUGGUUCUCGAGCCUGCCAUUCAAAACCAAAGCAAAUUGGAGCAUUUCUCACAACAUGGUAUUGAAGUUCCUUUUUGUUCUCAAAAGUUGUGACCGUGUUAAAUUGUACUCCCUUAGUCCUGUAAGGUAUGUUAAGUGAAUCGCAGUUACGCUGUACUUUUAUUAAUAUUUAACAUAAUUAAAGAUGGACCCAUAAGAGUGA